AGUCCCGCUCAGCCCGGGCACAUCCUCCGGCUGCCCGCGCACCUCUCCACGCCGGCCCCGUUCCGCGGCUCGCCCUCGGCUGCGCUCGGCUCCCGCGGGCGCUCGGCCCCGAGCCCCUCCUCCCCCUACCCGCCGGCCGGACAGGGAGGAGCCAAUGGCUGGGCCUGCCAUCCACACCGCUCCCAUGCUGUUCCUCGUCCUCCUGCUGCCCCUGGAGCUGAGCCUGGCAGGCGCCCUUGCACCUGGGACCCCUGCCCGGAACCUCCCUGAGAAUCACAUUGACCUCCCAGGCCCAGCGCUGUGGACGCCUCAGGCCAGCCACCACCGCCGGCGGGGCCCGGGCAAGAAGGAGUGGGGCCCAGGCCUGCCCAGCCAGGCCCAGGAUGGGGCUGUGGUCACCGCCACCAGGCAGGCCUCCAGGCUGCCAGAGGCUGAGGGGCUGCUGCCUGAGCAGAGUCCUGCAGGCCUGCUGCAGGACAAGGACCUGCUCCUGGGACUGGCAUUGCCCUACCCCGAGAAGGAGAACCGACCUCCAGGUUGGGAGAGGACCAGGAAACGCAGCAGGGAGCACAAGAGACGCAGGGACAGGUUGAGGCUGCACCAAGGCCGAGCCUUGGUCCGAGGUCCCAGCUCCCUGAUGAAGAAGGCAGAGCUCUCCGAAGCCCAGGUGCUGGAUGCAGCCAUGGAGGAAUCCUCCACCAGCCUGGCGCCCACCAUGUUCUUUCUCACCACCUUUGAGGCAGCACCUGCCACAGAAGAGUCCCUGAUCCUGCCCGUCACCUCCCUGCGGCCCCAGCAGGCACAGCCCAGGUCUGACGGGGAGGUGAUGCCCACGCUGGACAUGGCCUUGUUCGACUGGACCGAUUAUGAAGACUUAAAACCUGAUGGUUGGCCCUCUGCAAAGAAGAAAGAGAAACACCGCGGUAAACUCUCCAGUGAUGGUAACGAAACAUCACCAGCCGAAGGGGAACCAUGCGACCAUCACCAAGACUGCCUGCCAGGGACUUGCUGCGACCUGCGGGAGCAUCUCUGCACACCCCACAACCGAGGCCUCAACAACAAAUGCUUCGAUGACUGCAUGUGUGUGGAAGGGCUGCGCUGCUAUGCCAAAUUCCACCGGAACCGCAGGGUUACACGGAGGAAAGGGCGCUGUGUGGAGCCCGAGACGGCCAACGGCGACCAGGGAUCCUUCAUCAACGUCUAGCGGCCCCGCGGGACUGGGGACUGAGCCCAGGAGGUUUGCACAAGCCGGGCGAUUUGUUUGUAACUAGCAGUGGGAGAUCAAGUUGGGGAACAGAUGGCUGAGGCUGCAGACUCAGGCCCAGGACACUCAACCCCAGGAGGGGAGCCGCUCGGCGAAUGAGCUGGGUGGGUGCCCAGGAGCCGGCCCGCAGCACCUGCACACACGAAGUCCGGACCCACGCAGCCUCCAUCCCGCGUGUCUUGCUCUCCGCGAUGGCAAUGCCGAGAGUGCCCUCUACUGUCCGACUCCAGCACUGCAACAGCUUCAAGUUCAAAACCAAGAGGCGUUUUUGAGAGUGGAAAAGAAAUUUAAACUUCCCGAAAGAAGGUCCACCAUCAGGAGAUGAAUAUGGAACAUCUCCUAUGUACCAGGCACUGUGCUAAGUGCUGGAAUACAUUAUCUCAUUGAAUUAUCACAACGACCUUUUCAAGUAGGCAUUAUCACCAUGCGACAGGUUGAGGACCGUGAGGCACGCUGGAGUUAUUUGACUCGACUUGCCCAGGGUCCCAGGUCAGUGCUCCUCAAACCUGAACAUGCUAAGAGUCACCUGGAGGUCCAGUUAAAAAUGUACAUCUGGCCGGGCGCGGCGGCUCACGCUUGUAAUCCCAGCACUUUGGGAGGCCAAGGCGGGUGGCUCACCUGAGGUCAGGAGUUCGAGACCAGCCUGGCCAACAUGGGGAAACCCCGUCUCUAUUAAAAAUACAAAAAUUAGGCCAGGCGCGGUGGUGCACACCUGUAAUCCCAGCUACUCGGAGGCUGAGGCACCAGAAUCGCUUGAACUUGGGAGGCAGAGGUUGCAGUGAGCAGAGAUCGUGCCACUGCACUCCAGCCUGGGGGACAAGAGUGAAACUCCAUCUCAAAAAAAAAAAAAAAAAAAAGCACAUCUGACUCAGUGGGCUCUGUGCUCUAACAAGCUCCCAGGGAACGCGAGGCUGCUGGCCCAGGGACCCACUGAGAGGUCCUGGGAAGUACAUGGCAGAGCAAGGACAUGAACCUGGGCCAAGGCUGUCCAGCUCCAAGGCCCACGUUCUUGCUGCUCCACAGCCAAGAAUUUCUUCCAGAUUCUCUAAGGCUUUUGGCAAGAGAGGCUCACACCCUGGUAUUCCCUUCCUCUGUGGCUGGAAUAACUUGACUGUUCUCUGCCUUCCCUGGAUAAAGGUGUAUCAUGUUUAAAAACAAAACAAAAUACAACUUAAGCACAUACUUGCUUGCAGGAAUAAGUUGGGCAGGUUGAUCCCUGUGGUCUAGUAGCUGAUAUCCUGGGAUAAGAAGUGUUUGGGGAAAAGAAUCAUGUUGGCCUUUAUGUCCCUGUGGUCCUGAUCAUCCAGUCCUGGACAGGCACUUUACAGUUUUCUGGAGCACUUCCCCCCCAGGGGUUCUGAUGCAAGCAUGGAAUCCAAAAAAACCCCACACAUAUUGCCCAUGUUUACCCACUUUGCAUACUGUUUAGUGAUUUCCAGGACCACAAAACCAUCCCUGGAACCCCACCCCACAUUUUUGCAGCAGAGCCCACUGGGAAGUUGAGGCUCACCUGAAAUUGAGGUGCUAUCUGAAGCUAACUGCCCCUAACAGGCCAGACUCACAAUGCCCACCCAGGACAUCUGUCCCAGCAGAUCUGGCUUCAGGGGUCACUUCAGGAGAACCAUUUAAAUCCCCCCACUUGGCAUCUCACUCCUGGCCAACCCUCUGUUCCAGGGCGAACCAGGUUGCAAAUGACAAAAGACUUUCCUGGCCAAAUUCCUCACUGGCCUGGAUCACGCCCAUAAGAUGCCAGAGAUGUUUACUGCGUUGGAAAAAUCAGUCGGGGUCAGGGGUCAGGCACCAAGGAAAGCAGGCAGAUCUAGAAGAAAUUAAAUAUGCUUGUUCUCUCCCUAUCCAAGUUUGAUGGGCAUGGGAACCUUGUGGGGAGGGAGCAGGGAGGGCAGGGGAACUGGGAGAUCAAAGCAGGCUAGCUGAAAGGCAGAUAUGGCUAGACACAAUGGCUCAUGCCUGUAAUCCCAGCACUUUGGGAGGCUGAGGUGGGCGGACCACCUCAGGUCAGGAGUUUGAGACCAGCCUGGCCAACAUGGCAAAACCCGGUCUCUACCAAAUAUACAAAAAUUAAGGCUGGGCACGAGGGCUCAUGUCUGACAUCCCAGCACUCUGGGAGGCCGAGGUAGGCAGAUCACUUGAAGUAAGGCGUUCGAGAACAGCCUGACCAACAUGGUGAAACCCCAUCUCUACUAAAAAUACAAAAAUUAGCCAGGCAUGGUGGCAGGUGCCUGUAAUCCCAGCUACUCAGGAGGCUCAGGCGGGAGAAUCACUUGAACCCAGGAGGCGGAGGUUGCGGUGAGCCAAGAUCACGCCAUUGCACUCCAGCCUGGGCGACAGAGUGAGACUCCAAAAAUAUAAAACACUUAAAAAUGUAAAAAGGCAGAUCUGCCAGCAGCUUCGUACUUGAGACCAGACAACCCACACAUGCUGUGUGUGCCUCACAUUAAGUGGUGACUCGGGACUGUGCUGGCUCUGUGGGGCUAGAACCCUAAGGAGUACCGCCGGAAGAAAGCCCAGCAUUACUAUGGCUGGGGGACAGCUGUUAGAUGGUCCUAGGACAUCAGCCAUGGAGAACACAGAGGGUCAGGACAAAGCUAAAAUGCCCAUAGAACUGCCACUGGUUGCCAGGGUAGUUCCAUGGUUGGAAAUUCAAGGCCCGUCUCUUUGCCCUAGCUAUCUCUAUUUGACAUUUCCAAAGAGGGAUGGGUGGAUGGAACCUCUUAACUCCAGAGCUGGGAAUCCCAAAGCCCUCUCAAGUGUCUAACCAACCUCUCUGCCAGGAAGUUCUUCCUUAGGUCUAUCUUAAAUUUAUUUUGCUCAUACAGAAGCCAGUUUCCUCUAAUCCAGGGUUUAGCAAACUUUUACUGUGAGGAGCCAAAUAAACAUUUUAGGAUUUGCAAGCCAUCUGAUCUCCACCAGCUACUCAGCUCUGCCGUAGCUCGAAGCAGCCACAGAGAGUGUGUAAAUGAAUUCAUGGCUAUGCUCCAGGAAAACUAUUUCUGGACACACAUGUGAAUUCUGUAUACUUUUCACAUGUCACAAAAUAUUAUUCUCUCUUUCCUUUUUUUUUUUUUUGGAGAUGGAGUUUUGCUCUGCUGCCCAGGCUGGAAUGCAGUGGCUCAGUCUCAGCUCACUGCAACCUCUUCAUCCCAGGUUCAAGCAAUUCUCCUGCCUCAGCCUCCCAAGUAGCUGUGACUACAGGCAUGUGCCACCACACCUGGUUAAUUUUUGUAUUUUUAGUAGAGAUAAGGUUUUACCAUGUUGGCCAGGCUGGUCUCAAACUUCUGACCUCAGGUGAUCCGCCCGCCUCAGCCUCCCAAAAUGCUGGGAUUACAGGUGUGAGCCACCGCACCUGGCCAUAAAAUAUUAUUAGUUUAAUUUUCUAAAACCAUUUAAAAGUGCAAAAACUGCUCUUUGCUUGCCAACUGCGCAAAACCAGGCAGUGGGGCAGAUUUGGCCUGAGGGUCACGGUUUGCCAACCCCUGCUCAAGCCUGCUCACUCUCAACGCUGGCUGCACGUUGCAAUAAUCCAGGAACAUUCACAGGCCUGGGGCCCACCCACAAAGCUUCUGUUUUGUUUGGUCUGGGCUUCAUAGUUUUUCUCCCAGGUAACUUCAGGUGCAGCUGGGGCGGAGAGUCUCUGCUCUCCCCUUCCAUCUGUAGCAGUGUGGCUGGUGUUAAAUCCACCUAUUCCACCUCUCACAGCUUUGGCAACCUUAGGAAAGUUUCUUAAGGUCUCUGUGCCUUGAUUUUUUCAUCUGUAAAAUGGGAAUAAUAACUCUCCCUUCAUAGGGUUGUUGUGAGUAGUGAAUGCAUACUUCUUUUUUUUUUUUUUUCUUUUGAGACAGAGUUUCACUCUUGUUGCCCAGGCUGGAGUGCAGUGGCACGAUCUCGGCUCACUGCGACCUCUGCCUCCUGGGUACAAGUGAUUCUCCCGCCUCAGCCUCUCGCGUACCUGGGAUUAUAGGCAAGCAUCACCACGCCCGGUUACUGUUUGUAUUUUUAGUAGAGAUGGGGUUUCACCAUGUUGGCCAGGCUGGUCUCAAACUCCUGACCUCAGGUGAUCCCCCCGUCUCAGCCUCCCAAAGUGCUGGGAUUACAGGCAUGAGCCAGCAUGCCUGGCCUGUGAACGCAGAAUUCUUAUAAGGUGUUUAGAACAGUGCCUAGCACCUAAUAAACCUCCAGUGUUAGCUAAUUUGUUAUUCUAGGAGAAUUUUAGAUGUCGGUUCUUUGACAAUGACCCAUCACAUACUCUGAGAUCAUUUCUAAGUCACCAUUCAAGCUCCUUCCCCAAAGUGUGUUCCAUAGAACACUGGGACCAUGAGAUGCUCUAUUAGAAAGGGUCAGGGUACGGUUCCAUGGUCAGAGAGGUUUGGAAAACUGUUCUGGCCUCAGCCCUUGGCAGCAUGUGCAGAUUCCAGGCACCGAGGCAGGGCUGGAGGAGUAAGUGGCUUUGCAAUAAAAUGGGUGCUGGAGUCUAAAAUGAUACCCUGGGUGGAGUGGGGGAGCUGAGCAGGAGGCCAGGUGGCAACCAGUAGCUGCUGGGCCCGUGGCCUGAACCCUCCUGCACUCCUCCAGCUGGAGUCUCACCGCGGAUCCCAGGAAUACCUGCUGUUCCCACAGGGCUGCCUUUCCGUAGUUUGUCUGGAGACACCAAGAGUGGUUUCCAUGCCUGCUGGGAAUAGGCUGAGCAUGCAAUGACAUGAGGGCCAAGGCUUGUGGGAAAAUGACAGCUUCACAGCCCCUUGAGGAGUGACCAAGCCACAAAGUAAAUCCUAAAGCCACAACCCCUUCUACCACUGAGCUGCUGGAGGUGGGUCCUUAUUUCAAGCCAUAUUCAACCCACCCAACAAAACCUAACAUUGAGGUGGUGGGCACACGGCCCCUGCCGUGGGGCUCACUCUGCAGCUGGAGAGACAGCAUACCUGAAACCUGCAAGGAACCGGUUUAUAAAACAACAGAACAGCCAGGAAAAUGGUGCUAGGAGAGACAGUGGAGAGGCCAGAGAAGCAAACCACUGUGGCUCCUCACUGGGGGUUUCACGGGGUUGGACUGAGCCCUGUCACCUCUGUGAUAGUCUUCACUCUGACAGGCAAUGGUGACUGUGUGUGUUUCCUGGGGAGGAGGUUAGCAGGGACGGUUGCCUUUCCUGGGAAGGGCAGUUUGCAGAACCAGGGGUUUAUAUUGCAGGGAGUGUAUUUUCUGAAUUCUAAGUCAGAACAAGCAGUCUGAUACAGGAUCCAUGGCUGGGUCACUUCUGGGUGCAAGAGGCUUUCUAGACCUUAGACACUCAAGAUUACGGUCCCGGGCCAGUAACAGCACCUGGGAGCUUGGUAGAAAUGCAGAAUCUUAGCCUAGGCAACAUAGGGAGACCUCAUCUCUGCAAAAAAUAACAAAAUUAGCCGGGCAUGGUGGUGCACACCUGUAGUCCCAGCUAUUCUCCAGGCUGAGGUGGGAGGAUCGCUUGAGCCCAAGAGGUUGAGGCUGCAGUGAGCCAUGAUCGCACCACUGCACUCCAGCUUAGGCAAUACAGCGAGACCUUGUCUCAAAAAAAGACAAAAAAAACAAAAAGAAAUGUAGAUUCUUGGGCCCCACCACCCCACGCCUACUGAGCCAGAAUCUCUGGGGGUGGGGCCCAGCCAUUUGGCUUUUCACAAGUUCUCCAGGUCAUUCUUGGGCACGAUCAAAUUUGAGAAUCACAGGUCUAGGAUACGACGGGGAAAACAGAAAUGUGGGGUGGUCAGGGACAUUCGGAUAAUUCGGGCUAUUUGUAUUCAGGUGUGAGCUGGCAAAUCCGAGACCUGUUUUGCGUAGCUAAUUACCAGCAAUGACAAACUCCCAGGCUCUGAGGCCCAAGCCUCCUGGGCUGCAACUGGUCUUUAUUUUUGGAGGCAAUGAAUGGAGCACCUCGGCCUGGGACCCUCAGUGUAGGGUUUUCUGACUCUUAGGCAACUUCCUAGGGUGCUGUACUUCCUUUUUAAAGUUGGGGAGCGGCAGGGGGAGGGGGAAGUGCCACGCCCUUGUAGUUUCAUGAUGUCAUGUUGCAUGUGCUCUUGAGCUGUAAAUAAAGAGACGAUGGUUAAAAAGCC